GUCCCGGCCAGAGGAGGAGCUCGCUGCCGGGGGACGCUGGGCUGAGCGGCCGGCGGCGCGGGCCCGGCGGCGGCGGCAGCGGGGUCCGGGUCCGGAGCGCCACAGAAAAACAUAGAACGGAAAGCCCAGCCCAUCCUUGUUGGCUGUCAUACACGAGUGCUGUCUCCAAGGGAGUCACAGGUGUCUCAGAUGUGAGAGGAUCCCGGGGAGAUUGAGCUUACUGCCUGGGAACUUUUGGAUUUCUGGAGAAGCAGGCUGUGGUAGCCUGGCUCUGCGUCAGUGAAUACCUGGGAAAGGAGCUGGAGCUCUAUUUUGCUUGCUUUCUGCAUUCGUUUCUUUUAGAGCUAAUGGGGACACAAUAUUUUGAAGUUUUUCCAUUUCGGGUCUACAGCAUUUAGUGGUAUUUUCCUUAUAGUUAUGUUUUCCAAAUACUUCUCAAUUUCUUUGGUUCUGACAUUUCACAAUGAUUUUAAAAAAAUGUAAUAUGGAAAUUAAACUUGAGGUUUUCAGAAGCUGCUUUCAAGGUGUCUAGAUACAGAGUGAAGAAUGUCACAGUAGGAAGUGCACUGGACUAGGGGAGUCAGGAGACCCGGGUUCUUGUGUUGGCACCAUCACUCAUGAGCUACGAGGUGACUUCAGGCAAGUCCUCUCUGAGCCCCAGCUUAAUCAUGGCACAAUUGUAGGAUUGCUUUGAGGGUCAGACGAGAAUAUAGGAAAGAACUGCAAAAGCUGUAAAGCACUUAGGAGCUCUGGGAGAGUUGAGAGCUUCAAAGCCAAGGAAGACAGCCCACACUUCAGAAGAAGUGCUGCAGCUGCACAUUUGUUCGUUUAAUCAGGAAUUGUUUAUGAAGCAAUGUGUGUUACAUGCUGGGUGUGAGUACCUCUCUACUCCUUCCCACUAGAGCAGAGAGCUUUUAGUCUGGGAUGGAAGACGUAUUAAAUACAGACUUAUACAAAUAAUUGUUAUUAAUAUAAUAUGUAAUACAGUGCAAUUAAAAACAAUAAUUCAUAUAAGACACAUGUUAAAUGCACACUUACACAAAGAAUUGUUACAAGUAUCUCGGGUGUACAGGGCGGUUUUAUUCCUGCGAAGUGCUUCCUGGCUUGAGUGAAUACUUUUAUGGUGCUGGAGUUGAGAGAUAACACAGUUAACUGUUGAAAUUGGGCCAUUCCCGUUUCACAGGCUGCCAUUGGACCUGUCAAGUGCCUGAGUCAUGUGAUAAUGGGCUACAUUGCGCAGGGCCCCUGGGCCAUCUCCACAGGAGAUGCCAGAGGACGAGUGCCCACUUGCUGGUCUUCACAGAGCACGCUGAAAGUAAGAGGCAUGUGGGAAACUGACCAGGGCGGUUAGCUGACUCCAAAAUUGUCCAGAUUAGCAAAACUGCCCUCUGUGGAUCUUUGUUAAAGUUGGGUAUGGUAUUGUAGCAGUUUCUCCAGUCAGGUACCUUGUACUAGCGAGUCAACUUGAUUUUUUUUUGAAAAAGCAAUUAUUUAAUAAUAAUAUUUACUUCCAGGAAUUCUAGGUACUUAUUGUCUUCAUCUUGUCCAUUUAGGUCUGUAACCUAAAAGUUUUAAAGGACUUUUUGGUAUGAAUUCUGAUUAGUAAAGGUAGAGGAAGAAAGGAAAUUAUUUGGUAUCCAUUUCAAAUGAUCCUGAAUGGUUAGGGUAAGCUUUGCUGCAGUGACAAAUAGAUCCAGACAUGUAAUGGCCUCACAAUAGACGUUUAUUUUUCAAUCCCAUAACAAUCUAAGGAGGCUACAGGUCAUGGUGGUGGUUGGAGUUUGUGUGUGUAGGUGUGGGGAGGGAGGGUUCUUUUUAAAGCAGUAGUCCGAGGAUUGAGGCUGCUGGAGGCUCUUCUAUUUUGAACACCCGGCUUCUAAGGAUGUCCUGGGAAUCAGCUUCCCAGUUAAGGGGAAGAGGAGAAGAGUGGAGGGCAGGUCUGGAAGAGGCGUGUGCUGCUGCUGUUCCCAUUGCAUUGGCUGGCACCCAGCGGUAAGGCGACAUCCACCUGCACGCAGGACUGGGAAGUAUAGCCCAGCUGUGUGCUCAGGGAGAAGAGCAACAACAUUCUUUGCAGCAAAACCUGAAACACUCAGUUUCACUUUCUGUGACUUGUUUUGUAAGUUGUUUUCAAUAAAGAAGAUUAAAAAAAGAAGCCAGGCAAAUGAAAGCAUAGGGGAGGAGUGGCAGACACGCAGUUCUCACUCUGCGACUGCAGGAGUGUCUCUUGUUUCCCCCUUGUGCACUUUGAGGAAUGAGGGGAUAGACGUGGUCCCUUCCUUUUAGUUCCCCGUAGCAGAGUUCUUGUAAGGACUCGUUCAGGGGAGACUGAUAAGGGUCUCAUCUCCAUCGGGGGACCUCACCAGGGCAUGGAGUGGGUCAGAGUGGGCUGGGAGGGGAUAGACUGUCAUCAAGGUGAAGAGAUUUGAGGGGUGGUGGAGGGCUAAACUCCAGAUCUGACCACUUCAAAGUCAGCAAAGGCCAGGAAUUGCUGGGGUAGGGCUAAAAGCUGAGGGUUAGCAAAGAGAGGUGGGUCCUGGAAUGGGGACCCCUGGGGUGGAGGACAGAGAAGUCACACUGUUAGAAAGCCGUCACAGAAAAGGCAGUGUGGGAAUGAGCUUACUUAAGCCUAGGGAAUAUUCAUUUGACAAAAUGGUUUGUGUACAUUCUGGUUUUUCUACCCUGACACCUGAGGGCUCUAACACAUUUCUGUUGGUUAUUGUGGAAGAGAGUGUCCAAGGGUGGGAGCACAGAUGCCGAAUUUGGUGUGUAGGAGACCAAUUUCAACAACUCUGGGGGCCUUGUAGAGUUUGCAAAGCCCCGUAAGUGAUUCUAAUCUCUCUGCACCCACAAGAACCCCUAGUUUAGACACAGCUUCCCUUUAUCUGUGGUCAUUCACCACAGAUAAUUUCAUUCCCUAAAGAAUCACAAGCAGCUUCUAACAGUAAAUGCCCUUUACAGGAGGUGUAAAGUGCACUUGCUGUGUAGAGAGGGAGGCAUACCAUGAGCUUUGCGUGACUCAGGGAAGGAGGAUUUUUAUGGAAGAAGUAGCAUUUGAGCAUUCUUAUUUUGAUAAAGUUAUUUUUGAACUGCUUUUUAAAAAGGUAUAUUAAUAAGAAUAGAAGGGUGAUUAGAAUUCUAGUGUAGUGUUUUGGUUUUAUUUUUAACCAUUUAGCAAGAACAUUAAUGCUAUUAAAACUGAUGUGCCUUAGGAGACCCUCAGAUUGGUGUGGUAGUCACAUAUUUCUUCUGACGUUUCUGUUGCUAGGUGUUGACAUAGAUUUAGAGAUAGGUGUUGUCACCCUCAAUGUGGGUGGCUUGAGUACUUACAUAUAUAUUGUCUCAUUCUCUGAAUUCAGCAUGGCAGGUUAUUAUAAUCCUCGUUUUCAUAAGCAAGGCUUUGGCGAUGAAUAUACCUGCCAAGUGUGGGUCUUCUCCUGCACCCCACAGCCUCGGAGGGGCUUUAAGGGAACAUUAAGUGUAAAGCGUGUAAUUGCAGAGGAGGUGGACACAGGGCUCCUGCGGAGGAGGUGGACACAGGGCUCCUGGCUCCCAGUUCAGAGCAUCACAGCACCUCUCUCUGAGACCAGAGAUACAGUGAGACGGUUUAAGCGGAAGCAUCUUACUGCCAUUGACUGCCAGCAUUUGGCUCGGAGUCACUUGGCUGUGACCCAGCCCUUCGGUCAAAGAUGGACAAACAGAGAUCCGAACCAUGGUCUCUAUCCUAAACCGAGAACAAAAAGAGGGAGUAGGGGUCAGGGAAGUCAAAGAUGCAUCCCUGAGUUCUUCCUAGCAGGCAAGCAGCCGUGCACCAAUGACAUGGCCAAAAGCAAUUCUGUUGGCCAGGACAGCUGUCAGGACUCUGAGGGUGACAUGAUCUUUCCUGCAGAGAGCAGCUGUGCACUGCCUCAGGAAGGCAGUGCAGGGCCGGGCUCACCAGGGUCUGCCCCGCCCUCCAGGAAGCGGUCUUGGUCCUCUGAGGAAGAGAGUAACCAGGCUACCGGGACCAGCCGGUGGGAUGGAGUUUCUAAGAAAGCUCCACGGCACCAUUUGUCUGUGCCAUGCACAAGGCCUAGGGAGGCCAGGCAAGAAGCAGAGGACAGUACGUCUCGGCUCUCUGCGGAGUCUGGUGAAACCGACCAAGAUGCUGGGGACGUGGGUCCUGAUCCCAUUCCUGACUCAUACUAUGGGCUUCUUGGGACCUUGCCCUGCCAGGAAGCACUGAGCCACAUUUGCAGCCUGCCUAGUGAGGUCCUGAGGCACGUGUUUGCCUUCCUCCCGGUGGAAGACCUCUAUUGGAACCUGAGCUUGGUGUGCCACUUGUGGAGGGAGAUCAUCAGUGACCCGCUGUUCAUUCCUUGGAAGAAGCUGUACCAUCGAUACCUGAUGAAUGAAGAGCAAGCUGUCAGCAAAGUGGACGGCAUCCUGUCUAACUGUGGCAUAGAAAAGGAGUCAGACCUGUGUGUGCUGAACCUCAUACGAUACACAGCCACCACUAAGUGCUCUCCGAGUGUGGAUCCCGAGAGGGUGCUGUGGAGUCUGAGGGACCACCCCCUCCUCCCCGAGGCUGAGGCGUGUGUGCGGCAACACCUCCCCGACCUCUACGCUGCUGCCGGGGGUGUCAACAUCUGGGCCCUGGUGGCGGCUGUGGUGCUCCUCUCCAGCAGUGUGAAUGACAUCCAGCGACUGCUCUUCUGCCUCCGGAGACCCAGCUCCACGGUGACCAUGCCAGAUGUCACCGAGACCCUGUACUGCAUAGCCGUGCUUCUCUACGCCAUGAGGGAGAAGGGGAUUAACAUCAGCAAUAGGAUUCACUACAACAUUUUCUAUUGCCUAUAUCUUCAGGAGAAUUCCUGCACUCAGGCCACAAAAGUUAAAGAGGAGCCAUCUGUCUGGCCAGGCAAGAAAACCAUCCAACUUACACAUGAACAACAGCUGAUUCUGAAUCACAAGAUGGAACCUCUCCAGGUGGUGAAAAUUAUGGCCUUUGCCGGCACUGGGAAGACCUCAACGCUGGUCAAGUAUGCAGAGAAGUGGUCUCAGAGCAGGUUUCUGUAUGUGACAUUCAACAAGAGCAUCGCAAAGCAGGCCGAACGCGUCUUCCCCAGCAACGUCAUCUGCAAAACCUUCCACUCCAUGGCCUACGGGCACAUAGGGCGGAAGUACCAGUCAAAGAAGAAGUUGAAUCUCUUCAAGUUAACACCCUUCAUGGUCAACUCCGUCCUUGCUGAAGGGAAGGGUGGAUUCAUAAGAGCCAAGCUUGUGUGUAAGACUCUAGAAAACUUCUUUGCCUCGGCUGACGAAGAGCUGACCAUUGAUCACGUGCCUAUUUGGUGUAAGAACAGCCAAGGACAGAGAGUCAUGGUUGAGCAGAGUGAAAAACUGAAUGGUGUCCUUGAAGCGAGCCGCCUCUGGGAUAACAUGCGGAAGCUGGGGGAGUGCACAGAAGAGGCGCACCAGAUGACUCAUGACGGCUACUUGAAACUCUGGCAGCUGAGCAAGCCUUCGCUGGCCUCUUUUGACGCCAUCUUUGUGGAUGAGGCCCAGGACUGCACACCAGCUAUCAUGAACAUAGUUCUGUCUCAGCCAUGUGGGAAAAUCUUUGUAGGGGACCCGCACCAGCAGAUCUAUACCUUCCGGGGUGCGGUCAACGCCCUGUUCACAGUGCCCCACACCCACGUCUUCUAUCUCACGCAGAGUUUUCGGUUUGGUGUGGAAAUAGCUUAUGUGGGAGCUACUAUCUUGGAUGUUUGCAAGAGAGUCAGGAAAAAGACUUUGGUUGGAGGAAACCAUCAGAGUGGCAUUAGAGGUGACGCAAAGGGGCAAGUGGCCUUGUUGUCCCGGACCAACGCCAACGUGUUUGAUGAGGCCGUACGGGUGACGGAAGGGGAAUUCCCUUCAAGGAUACAUUUGAUUGGGGGGAUUAAAUCAUUUGGAUUGGACAGAAUCAUUGAUAUUUGGAUCCUUCUUCAGCCAGAGGAAGAACGGAGGAAACAAAACCUCGUCAUUAAAGACAAAUUUAUCAGAAGAUGGGUGCACAAAGAAGGCUUUAGUGGCUUCAAGAGGUAUGUGACCGCUGCCGAGGACAAGGAGCUUGAAGCCAAGAUCGCAGUUGUUGAAAAGUAUAACAUCAGGAUUCCAGAGCUGGUGCAAAGGAUAGAAAAAUGCCAUAUAGAAGAUUUGGACUUUGCAGAGAUGGAGUCUCACCAUGUUGGCCAGGCUGGUCUCGAACUCCCAACCUCAGAGUACAUUCUGGGCACUGUGCACAAAGCCAAAGGCCUGGAGUUUGACACUGUGCAUGUUUUGGAUGAUUUUGUGAAAGUGCCUUGUGCCCGGCAUAACCUGCCCCAGCUUCCGCACUUCAGAGUUGAGUCAUUUUCUGAGGAUGAAUGGAAUUUACUGUAUGUUGCAGUAACUCGAGCCAAGAAGCGUCUCAUCAUGACCAAAUCAUUGGAAAACAUUUUGACUUUGGCUGGGGAGUACUUCUUGCAAGCAGAGCUGACAAGCAACGUCUUAAAAACAGGCGUGGUGCGCUGCUGCGUGGGACAGUGCAACAAUGCCAUCCCUGUUGACACCGUCCUUACCAUGAAGAAGCUGCCCAUCACCUAUAGCAACAGGAAGGAAAACAAGGGGGGCUACCUCUGCCACUCCUGUGCGGAGCAGCGCAUCGGGCCCCUGGCGUUCCUGACAGCCUCCCCGGAGCAGGUGCGCGCCAUGGAGCGCACUGUGGAGAACAUCGUACUGCCCCGGCAUGAGGCCCUGCUCUUCCUCGUCUUCUGAGGACAAGGCGCACGUUCUCCGCAGUGCAGAGCAGCUUGCCGAGGACCCCGCGUGAAGAAAGCCAGCGAGGGGGGCUUCUGCUCCCUGAGACUCUGGGUUCACCCACAGCACUUUCUGAGGAAGAGGACACCAGCCCAAGCUGGACCUGCCAUUUCUCCACUCCCUACAGACAGCCAGUCUCCACUUGCCUCCCCUCUGGAUGUAUCUGGUCAGGGAAGUGGGGGAUGUUCUUUUGAUAAAAAAAAAAAAAAAAAUUUAUGUAUUUAAACUUUUAUUACAAGAUUUCAAUUAAACAGGCACCAUAGCACUGGCA